CACAUGAAUGUCUAGUUGUUUCAGUACCAUUUGGUGAAAUUUGUUUGUUUUUUUUUUUUCUCCAUUGUAUUGCCUGUGCCCUUUUGUCAAAGAUCAUUUGACUAUAUGUGGGUCUAUUUCUGGCCCCUCUAUUCUAUUCUGUUGAUCUGUUUAUUUCUUCUUUCAUCAAUAACACAGUCUUGAUUAUUCUAGCUUUCUAGUGAAUCUUGAAGUUGGUUAAUGUCAGUCCUCCAACUUUGUUCUUCAGUAUUGUGUUGGCUCUUCUGGGUCUUUUGCCUCUUCAAAUUAACCUUAGAACAUUUCUUUCUUUUCUUUUCUUUUCUUUUUUUUUGAUACCCUUAAAAUAACUUGCUUGGAUUUUGAUUGUAAUUGCAUUGAAUCUGUAGAUUAAGUUGAGAAGGACUGCCUCCUUGGUAAUAUCCUUUUCAUGAACAUGGAAUAUCUCUCCAUUUAUUUAUUCUUUGAAUUCAGUUAUCAGAGUUUUGUAGUUUUCUUCAUACAGGUCUUGGCAUAUUUUAUUAGAUUUAUACCAAAGUAUUCAUUUUUUUCUGGGUGCUAAUGUAAAUAGUAUUUUUAAUUUCAAAUUUCACUUGUUCAUUGCUAAUAUAUAGGAAAGUGAUUGACUUGUAUAUUAACUUUGUAUCCUGCAACCUUGCUAUAAUUGCUUAUUGGUUCCAGGAUAUGCCACCUAUUUUUAGUCUUUUAAGUUAUUGCAGUUCUUAGAGAAUACAAUUACAACUCACUUACCCAAUGAUUUUUAUGUUCACAUCUUUUAAUUAUAUAAAACAGACGUAGUAGUUCUGUUGUUAAAGUAGGUUAAAUAUCUUUUGUGUUUUGGCUAUAAACUAUAAGAUUUAGAAAACCUGAAACAACUUAAACUUUUGCUACUUUGAGACUUGGGAUCUCAGUAUCUUAUUUCAAUUAAAAAAAUUCUUAAUCAUUAUGAAAAUCGAUGUGCUUGUAUGCUGCUAUUUCUAAAAAUGACUUUGUGAAAAGUGGCCUGGCAUGGUGGCUCAUGGAAGGCUAAGGCAGGAGGGUCACUUGAGGCCAGGAGUUUGAGACCAAUCUGGACAACAUAGUGAGACCUCUUCUUUACAAAAGGUUUUAAAAAUUAGUGAGGCGUGCUGGCAAGCACCUGUAGUUCCAGCUACUUGGGAGGCUGAGGUGGGUAGAUCACUUGAGCCCAGGAGUUUGAGAUUGCAGUGAGUUGUCAUCAGGCUGCUGUGCUCCAGCCAGGGAAACAGAGUGAGACCCUGACUCUUAUAAAACACAAAAAUAAAAACUAAAAAUGACUAUUUGAAAAGUAAAAAUAAAUACAUGGCAUUGAAAGUGUGCUUGAACUAGAAUUCUAUGAUUUUUAUAGUUUGAUUCAAGUUUCUGUGAUUCUGAUUAUGUAAAUUUGGAAAUACUGUUGAACAUUUAGCUGAAUGUACAUUAUGGGAUACAAAGAGAGGAAUAUUCAGUUUCUAUGGAAUUCAAGAAGGGUUUCAUAAAGAAAGGUUUGGAUUAGAUUUUUGAGGGUAAGUAGAAGUAUGUCCGUUGGGUAAGAAAUUGAAUUUUACUUUUCCUCAAUAACGAUAACAGCUGCAUUUAUUUUACAUUUAAUAUUUACCAGGUAUUAUUCUACAUUCCACUUAUAUUGACUCAUUUAAAUCUUUAUGAAGUAGUUAAAUUCUGUUUUUUUAAACCUUUAUCUUACAGAUGUAGAAAUGGAGGCUCAGCAAGAUUGGAGUAACUUCUCCAAAAUCACACAGCUAGAGAUGACAGAAUUUGACUUUUAACCCAGGCUUCUUGUCCCUUGUGCUGUUGUGCCAGUCUUUUGUUUGUCUUGAGUAAGAUUCACUUAUGAAAAAAUUGAAUUUCACAAGUUCAAUCUAGUGUUUGAAAUUCAAAAACAUUUUCCUAUAGAAAUCAUAAUUAGUAACGAUAUUUUUAGAAAAUGUUUCCCGAACCUAGUUAACACCUAAUAUAUCUCUAUAGUAUUCAAGCAAUUAAUCAUUACUAUCCGGCAUAGCAGUACUGAUUGACAUUUUUAACUAGGUGUCAAACACAUCUGCCACUGCUGCAGUAAGUCAUAAGAUUCUUUCAUAUUUCUUCUACCUUAACUGCAUCCACUGAAGGCACUGCUUUACACCAAAGCCUUAGUUUCUCUUAGGCCUGAAGAUGCACUUCUAGUAACACUGAUGAGUUGAAGAGCAAUUUGAGAAAUUGGGGAUGAGUUGUGCUGAACUUGAAUUUCUUAUCAGUGUAAGCACUUAGUGAGUUACACUUGUUCCAAGCCUAUCUCACGGUUAUCCCAGUUCUUUUCCUGAGGACUCUUCUUUCCACUUGGGCUAUUUUCAAUUAGAACUUUGUUUCUUCUUCAGGUUGCAAAGAAGAAUGUAAUCUUGUAGAGUACCUUGCCUUCCCUUCCAUACAUUCAGCAGACAUAGUUCCUUUAAGGGAUUUUACUGCUAGGAGAAUUUCAUAGGUCAUAUUCCCAUGUUACUGCUUCACAGGUAUUUACUUAUUUACUUACUUAUCACAGAAAUCCUUUAGGGGAAAGAGACAAUAAUGAUGGGAUGUUGUAAAUUUUUGGAAGUAGAGAGGUUCGGAUUGUGAAGAGGAGAUGAGAUAAAUAGUAAGUGGCACUGCAAAGAGAAAGGGAGAUUUUUCUCUACUAGUAGAAGUGGCUUAUGAAGAAGGAACUUCAACAAGCUGUUCUGCUCCAUUUUAUAAAUGUAUGAUUAUAGAUUGCCAAUAGUUAAUGCCGUGAGUACUUGAUACUGUAAGGCUAUGGCUGUUUUUAAAGUAAGAUUAAUACUUUUAUCUUUGUGAUAAGUAAUUAGAAGCCCUUUGAAAUACUAAUCUAAAUUAUUUGUUUAUAUAGCUAUCUUAUGUCUGCCCUUUACACAGCGCUUAGCUGAUUUUUGUUAUCUUUUACCUGGUGAUUGCCACCAUUUGCCCCAAUGUGCUGAACCACUUAGAAAAAGCAAUGCCAUAGUUUCCUGCUUUCUUUUUCUAAAAGAAAAAGUCAUACAGCAAGGUUCUGUUACUGAAGCCAAAACUUCAUUAACUUGAUUAUUAUUGAGUAUUUUUGUUAUUUCUGGAGAUUUUGGGCCUUUUUACAAUGAAUAUAAAUGAUCAAAUUCUUAUGGUUUAUGGGGAUAUGUAUUUAAGUAUUCGUGUUCCAUAACUAGAACCAUUUGUUUCUGCAUUCGCCCUUGGUCAAGAGAGAAAGCAUGACAUUUUUUUCUUGAAAGGUUUGUUUUUAUUGAUGGUUAAAUUUAUUACUAGAAUUUUAUUUGUUUAAAUUAAUGCAUACUUACUCCUUCCUCCCUUCCUCUGUGAGAUUAAUUAACAUCAGGACAAUGAAGCUUCAUUGUAUCAGUUAUUACUAGACAGUUUAGUUGUUUGGGUAGGAUAUUGCGUGUCGAAUAUAGCAGUCUUUUCUUAUCACAAUCUUUACGAAAAAGUAGAAAAGAGCCUGGAUAACUGGAAUUAGAAAUAAUUGCCAACAAAAUAUGUUUUCUAGUCAAUAGGGACAGAUAAGCACGCUUUAAAAACAUUCAUUGUACUGCAGGUCAUAACUUUAAUUGAGACAUUUAGUUCUUGAUGAUUAAAACUAUUUUCUAAUUUGAUUUCAACUAACAUUUACUGAAUGCUUAUUCUUGAUUUUAAUAGAGAGCUUCCCACUUAAUCAUUCUUAUCAGAAGUGUUUAAUGUCAUCAUAGUUCUUUCUCUUGAUAGCCACUGAAAAGAAAAUGUUCAGGUUAUAAAGAAAAUGAAUCAUUUAAAAAGAGAGAAUUGGCCACGUAUCUGAGAGAUAGAUCUUUUUUAAAACUAUGGAACUGUUGGCAUUCACAAGUCUUUCUUAAGAGAAAUUCCCACAAACUACUAAUUGAGGUGAAUAUGAUGGGUGGUAGGCUAGGUUUACUCCUUUAAUUUGGAACUCUGAUUUCCUUUCAGGUCUUAUAAAUAUUAGCUUAUUUAAUCUUUAUGAGAAUGGAUUAUUAUUCAUUGCCAUUAGCAAUAAUUACACAGGCUUUGAUGGUGGUUUAGAAAUGUUAAAUCUGUGAAUGCCAAUGAUUAAUUGUGUAUUUAGCUAAAAUAUUGCAAUCAUAGACAACAUGAUCUGUUUGGUAUUUUGGAGAUCAUUUGCCAGCUCUUGUCAUUUUGUAGAUAAGGAAAGAAUCCCAGGGAGAGCUUUUCUAAUUGCUGUGUAGCUAGUUAGUGACGGAACUACUUCGAUCCUAGUGUGUUUAAUUAUUUAAUGCAUUAAAAAUAUUCACAAUGAAUGCAUUUACCUAACUUAACAAAUUUUCUUGGCUUUUGUGUAUGGCUUAAAAUUUAAUUAAGCUGAAAUUUUUAUAUUAAAUUUAUUUAAUGAAGCUUUCUCAGUGCACUUUGAGCAAAGUUUUGAUUUUUAGUUUGUUAAAAGGAAAGGUGUUUUUGUUUUGUUUUGUUUUGUUUUUGUUUUUGAGACAAAUUCUUGCUCUGUUGCCCAGGCUGGAGAGCAGUGAGUGGUGUGAUCUCAGCUCACUGCAACCUCCCCUCCCAGUCUUGCGAUUCUCGUGCCUCAGCCUCCCAAGUAGCUGGGAUUACAGGCUGUCGCUGCCACUCCUGGCUAAUUUUUGUAUUUUUACUAGUGAGGAGGUUUCACCACGUUGGCCAGUCUGGUCUGGAAUUCCUGACCUUGAGUGAUCUGCCUGCCUCCAAAGCCCUGAGAUUACAGGCUUUAGCCACUGCACCUGGUCUUAAAAGGAAAGUAUUUGUAACACAAAGCUAUCUCAUUAAAAUGAGGAGAUUGUCUUGUAAAAACAGAUGUACUCCUUCCUUUGAGAAAGGAGAAAGCACAAUAUAUUGUCUUUUACUCUUAAAGUGAAUAAUUUUCUUUAUGCUAAAGUUUAGUGUGUGACACACAGUAGGAACCUGAAUGCAAUGAAGAACAGUGGGAAAAAUUUAUGCUUUAUCCAUUUAUUUUAUCAAAAGGUAAAGAUUUAUUCAACUUGUGUUUAAUAUCUGCCAUCUCCCACCCUCCUGGGAAUGGAGGCUGAAGAAAUGAGAUGAAUGCCAUUUUCAAGGGGGAGAGACCCUUAAGUUAGUGGUCACAAUUGAGCAUGAUACAGGUUAUUUUGGAGUUACGCAUAUGUUCUUUAGUAGAAGUUGGAAAGUCAAUGAACGUUUUAUAGUGCACAUGAAUGUUGAAGACUCAGUAGCAGUUGGUCUAAACAAACUGAUUUGUACAUGUCAAACAUGUCUUUUCAUUAAUUGAUUUUGGCUAAUGACUUCUUUGAAUACAUACCUGUAGAGAUAUUUUCUAUAAUGUCAGAAAAUACUCUUAAGGAAAAGUGACAGAAUUUAGGAAGCUUUCUUCCAUUGAACCUUUUAUUUGUUACUUUUUAGUACUGUAAUGAAACAUUUAUGCAUGUCUUGGCUAGAGAUUAAGUGGCUUGUUAAUAUGUUUAAGAAUAUUUUGUUCCUUGUCAACACUUUAAUGACUAUGGCAUUGCUUUAUAUGAGAUAUUACAUUAUUUAUUCAACCUCUUUUAACUGUGGAAAGUUAUCUUUUAAAAUAAACAACUGUUAAUUUGAACACCAAUAUGUUAAAAUGGUUUGUGACUUGUGUUUAAUUAGAAUGUUUUCUAUUGUUAUGAAAAAGUAUCUUUUUCCUUUCCCUCUUUGUUGUUGGUCUUCCAUUUGCCUUGUCAUUUAUACUGCGGAAAAUGUCUUUUUAUUUCUAAAUUUAAUCAAAAUCUGAUAAAUGACUUUAUAUUGUCAUCUUUAUCCGAAAGUCUGGAGCUGGUAUUUUUUAAGAUAGUUACAUCAAAUUCACACAUUCUACUGUUGUAGUUCUAAUCUUUAAAAAAUUUAGAAUGUAUCUAGGCAUUGAGGAUUUAUGCUUUUUGACCUUUGAAAGGGUCAAAAAGCUGUACUGAGGUAUUGAGGAUUUAUGCUUUUUGACCUUUGGAAGGACAUUAAAUUUCUUGUUUUUCUGAUUUAGAAAAUGGCAAAAAAAUUAUGCUUUCACUUUUUAAGGAAAUUAAAAAUGUAUUUUAUGCUGUAAAACAGUGCUGACAAACCCAAUUAAUUCUGUAAACAAUUAAAUUUGGAAAUAGAUAAAUCUGAGUUCAAAUUAUAGUUGUUGACAAUUAUGUUUUAUAAUUCUAUUUGUAAUAUUAAGAUGAACUAUAUGAAAUUGCCAUUUUGUAGGUCAAGACAAUUAAGUAUUAGCAAUUUCAUAGGAUUCAACCAAUAAAUGUACAUUAGAUAUCAAUAGGUGUUCUUAUUCUUUAGCUGCUUUUCUACCAAAUUCUUCUGUUCUUUCAUUUCAUAUUUAGUAUAGGCCCCCAUUUUUUACUUCCAGUCCAGUUUACUGUGUCUGUAAGCGCUGCAGGUAUGUUAGAAAACCAGUGAAGGCCACAGUAGUGGGAUACCAGAGAUGCUCUAUGGGAAGGAAGUCUGCUGGUCUCUUCAUGAUUGUUUUGUGCUGCUUUUAUCAGCUUUGGCAUUAUAUGGGAGAAUUUCUCUUCUGGAUUAGACAGUCCUCAGACCUACCAAAGAACCUAUUGGAAAUAACCAUCUUCAAAAACCCAGUUUGGGUCCAUCAGUUCCACAUACAUAGUUUCAUCACACUUUUCUUCUCAAGUUUCUAGACCUCUUAGUCACAUUGCCAGAGUGGUAAUUCUGGUUUUUAUCUUAUGACAUGACAUUUUUUUCCUCCUUUGAAGACCCUGAUCUUGGUGUGGUUAUUCUUCAAAUUUUUCUUUCAAACCUUGUCCAUUUUGGUGCUUUCUUUGGUUCUUUUGAUUACCCACUUAAUCAUCCUGGAUUUUCCUAUUCUUGUAACCUGUAUAAUGUCCCAUGAUGAUCAAUCUUUUUUUUUUUUUUCCCUUAAAAUUUUUUUUACAGUUACAGAGGGUCUCACUUUGUCAGGCCGGAGUACAGUGGUGCACUCAUGGCUCACUGCAGUCUCAACCUACUGGGCUAAAGUGAUUCUCUCACCUCAGCCUUCUGAAUAGCUGGGAUUACAAGCACAUGCCACCAUACUCAGCUAAUUUUUUUGUUUUUACUUUUGGUAGAAGGGUGUCUCGCUAUGUUGCCCAGGCUGGUCUUGAACUUCUUGCCUCAAGUAAUCCUCCUGCCUUGGCCUCCCAAAGUGUUGAGAUUAUGGACAUGAGCCACCACAUCCUGCUAAAUCAAUCAUUUUUCUGAUGUUUUUACCUAAUAUGCUGAAUCAUGCAGAUUUGCAGGUGCUUGGCAAUCAUUCAAUCAAUUCUAUGUUCCUCUUUUGUCAAAAUUUUCACAAAUUUUAGCUGUCCCUUCUUCCUCUCCUUUCUUUUACAGCUCAACUCCUUACCCCAUUGUGGUUCUUAGGAGAUGAUCUGAGAAUUUUGAAUUUUGAAAUUUGAAAUAAUCUAUAAUAAGUUCUUCAAAUAACUCUAUCUACUGGAAGGUAGGACAUCUAGAACGUUGACCUAGUUUUUCAACUACCCUGAUCAAAUUCAUAUAAACUGUGAGACCUCUGUUUUCAGAAUUAAUACAUCUCCAUACCUAUAUGUGCUUUCAAUUCAGUAGGAUAUAUGAGAUCUUGUAAUAGAUAAACUUUUUUAUGUUUUUGAUCUCAUCUAUUUCUGACCCUUAAGCAGUUAAAUUCCCACAUUUAACUCUUCAGCACCUCCCUAAUGUUGGUUCCUUCCCUUUUGCUUCAAGCAUGUACAUUUCUCUCUUAUAAUAAAUAUAUUUUAUAUAUAUAUGUAUUCUAGUAACUGUCAGAUUUUUCUUUUAUUGCUUAGUUUAUCCAAUGAUUAUGCCCAUUAUUUCCAUUUUAUCUUUACAUAAUCACCUAAGUCUUAUUUUACUGAAACUUACAGAGAUAAUUACUAAUCUCAUGCCUAAUUUAUUUUUUCUCUAAAAGUUUUAAUUUUAAAAAUUUUGCUUUUGAUUUAAAAGCUGUUUUGCUUCAAGCUUUUAUGGUAUUGCUUGGACUAUUUCAGUGGAUUUCUAAUAUAGUUCCUUGCUUCCAAUUACUUUUACCCCUUCAAUUUAUUUUUCCCAUUAUAGUUGCAGAGUCAUUUCUCCAAACAUAUUUGAUUUGGUUACUUCCAGGCUUUAUAUCCUGGGAUUAUUUCCAAGUACUUGCAGAAGAAUCCAUUGUGUGCAACCCAUACUAAAGUCUAGCCAUGUGGAACUUCACAUUAUUUCUGGAUUGUGCCAUUUGUUCUCCUUGUCUUUGUACGGGUAGGUAUAACUGCCUGACCUUCUCUUCCUUUCCUGUUCUGAUAGUGGAAUACUCUUUUUAACCUUGUCAAACUAGUUCGGAUGUCACCUCUGUGAACCAGUAUUUCAUAGACUUCCCUUGUAUAUUUAAUCACUCUAUUGGAGUGUUCCCAUAACACUGGAGAUUGAUCUCUACCAUACCACUUAUAUUUUAUUUGUAGGUGGCAGUGAGGAGUGAUUAACACUUAAAGUGUUUGAUAAAAUCCACAUACGAUGAAAGAAAUAAGUUAAGUAUUCCCUCCAGGACCCAUGGUAGACUAGAUUGUAGCCAAAUUAAUGGUAUUUACAUAUCCAAAGAGAGUAAUUUUUAGAUAGGUUUUAUCUAAAGAAAGAGUGUAUCAAUAAAAAUAGCUAGAAUUGAAUGUAAUUUACCCAAAAUUAUUUGGGGUUUGAGAGUAUUCUACCCUCUAGUGUGGUAUUUUGUAUAUUUCAUCAGACUUUCAUCACUCCUUGAAUGAAAUAUGCUUUAAUGAUAUUUGCUGCUUUCUGCCCUAAAUCACUACUCACCAAGCAUCCUGUUUCUAAUUUGGCUUCCAGUAUAUCAUUAAGACAGUAAUCGAAUGGAACACUUAGUAAACCUAAAUAUCUGAUCCACUUCAUAGUUUGUUUCACUGUAUGUUAAGUGACAAAACUCUUACAAACUUAUUACAACCAGUCUCCAAUACAUAAAGAUUGAUCAUCCUUUAUGUAUUAGCAAAAGCCUAUUUGCCGUGUGUUCGGAAAAGCCGAGGAUGCACCCAAGGUGCUUUCCUUGGGAGGCCUAUCUGAAGCUUGUCAGCCUUCUUCGUGAGUUUCUUUCAGUCUACACCUUUUCCCGUCAGUGGUUCUAGUAUUCUACCAAUCAUCCAAACUAAAACAUCUUGAAAUAACCUUUGAAACAUUCCUCAGUUUUAUUCUACAGUUGUUAUACUUUAUGUUCAGUCACAUUCAGAGUUUGAUUUUCUUCUGAAGUAGAUUUUUGUUCUUUCCUUUUGUUUCAACGACAUUUAUCUUAUUCUUAGUUUUUAUCUUUAAUUGAUUAAUAUAUCGCUAUAUCUAAUUUUCAUUAUGUGUUACUUGAAUUAUUUCAGCUCCCUGCCCCUGCCUGUUUAGAAGUCCUAGGUGAUCUUUCUAUUAAACAUUUCAGCUAAAUACCUUCUCUUGGUUUUAAAGACUCAAGGAGCUAAAAUUCAGUCUUCAUCCUAUUUUCCACAGUUCCUUUUUAUUUAGUAAGUUUGCUUUGGUUGAGGUAGGCGUUUUGCUGUUGCAAAUACCUUCUGUGUUCACACUUGUCAUUUAGCCUGAAAUUCCCUUCUCUUUACUUUUCUGUGAUUUUAGUUUCUGUCUUUAGGUUUCAUCUACUCUAUGAAACUUUAUCCAAUUUAAAAAAAUUCUACAACCCAUAUUCAUAGUACCGUGCAAUUUUGUGCUCAAAUAUUAUUUUAAUAUGUAUAUUUAUUGUUACGUAAUAUGUUAAUCUUGGGUUUUAAGCUCUGUUAAGACAAAUUCUUUUAUAGUAGCCCUGUUCAUUCAUUCAACAAGUAAUCAAGUGUGCUACUAUGAGCCAUCAACUAUUCUAAAUGACAUUGCUCUAAGUGUUUGGGAUAUAACAGUGAACACAAACAUCUUUGUGCCAAGUGCCUGAUGAUAGCCAGGAAGAUACUGGAUGUAUAUUAGAUAGACAGCAUGUUCUUGUUAGUUGAAUUUUCAUAUGCUUUUUCUAUUUAUAGAUAUAAUUUCUGUGGCGACAUAAUUUGGAUUUACAGUGAUUUUUAACAUUGUUUAAGAUCAUAAAUCAUUUGUUAUAUUGAUAUAUAGUUCUUUUUGAAACUACCUUUGCAAAAUUAUGACAGCAAGAGAAAUCUGACAUAGUUGACUCCCAUCUUGCUUCUAACCUCCAGGCUGUUCUAGGUCAUUUUUGGGCAUUGGCCAGGCUAACCUUGGGAGGCAUUUAUUUUAUAGUUUAACUUUGAAGCUAGGAUGAUAAUAGUUCCUUCCUAAAACUAAUCCCCCCUGUUGAAACAAUCUGAAACUGCCUUUUAAGACUAGUGAAAGACCGCAAGAUUAGAAUUGUGGGAGGAGCUUGAGUUCUGUUAAGAUGUAGGUGUAGUUUUUAUAAUCCCUUAUUGCUCAGGAGUCAUGUGGCCAGAAGUCACAAGAUUUGUGACUUCCCCAGUUACUCCUACAGAUAACAUCACUAUUGUAAUACCUAAGAUUGGUUUUUUUGAGAUGUUUUUCAGACUAACCACAUGCAGACCCAUGAUUCAUGACUCAUCUGGUCCUGUGGCCCAGUUGAGUAUAUGAGGCAGACUCAGUAUAUGAGGACCGUUUUCUUUACCCCUAUGAUUUCAUCCCCAACUAAGCAGCAGUCUCCAUUCCCUAGCCCCCCUGUCCACCAAAUUGUCCACAAAAGCUUUAGCCUCUGAGACUUUGGGCAGUGAUCAGUCUCACUCAAAUCAGUCGCUUCUCACUCAAAUCAGUCUCACUCAGUCAGUUGAGCCAUUUCUUCCAUGUAGUUGGCCUUGCAUUAAUUAAACUCUUUAUUGCAGUGCCGUGAUCUCUGUAAGUUGAUUUUGUCUAUGCAGCAGUCAGGAAGAGCCCAUCAGGCAAUUACACAUUUAGGGGCUUGUCCAAGAUCUGCCCUUCUGGGUGCCUGUCUGCUAUCUCUCAGCCUUCCACUGGUACAAUGGAACUGGGAGUGAGCUCGGGCGUUUCUUAUUUGUCUCGAACUGAGGGCCAUCUCUGAUACGGUCUCUGCCAAUGAGACGCGGUCAACCCAUAGUGCUUGGGCCUAAUUGCAGUGAAGAAACAGUUACUGGAAGAUGUCUUUAAACUAGGCUGGUGAGUGUACAAAGCACUACCAACAUCCUCUUCCUUCUCCUGUUCUGGUUGGCGCCUUUUGGGCCAACCUAGCUCUCCUUAGAUUGUACAGAGAGUCUUGGUUUAGGGAGAUUUCUCUCCACUUAGAUGGAGAACAGGGGCUUGUUUGGAAAAACACUUUUCUGGUCAGGAUUCUGGUUCUGAGAGGCCUCUUGUCUGUCUUUGUCUGUGUUCUUAUAUGUAUAUCACUCUGGCUGGAAUGGGAAAUAUUAAUGAUAGGCUUUUUAUAGUUCUAUGAAAUGGAAAAAGGAUGAUUUUUCUUUUGUAACACGUCUUGGCCCCCACAGCUAUAGCAGAGCAUGCAGGGUCACCAAAGCCACUCAGGAAGAGGGAACCAGAAACCUGGCAAGCUAACAAAAAGGGUGUGAUAGGUAUACAGCUGGUUGUUACCAUGGUGAUGGCCAGUGUCAUGCAGAAGAUUAUACCUCACUAUUCUCUUGCUCGAUGGCUACUCUGUAAUGGCAGUUUGAGGUGGUAUCAACAUCCUACAGAAGAAGAAUUAAGAAUUCUUGCAGGGAAACAACAAAAAGGGAAAACCAAAAAAGAUAGGAAAUAUAAUGGUCACAUUGAAAGUAAGCCAUUAACCAUUCCAAAGGAUAUUGACCUUCAUCUAGAAACAAAGUCAGUUACAGAAGUGGAUACUUUAGCAUUGCAUUACUUUCCAGAAUACCAGUGGCUGGUGGAUUUCACAGUGGCUGCUACAGUUGUGUAUCUAGUAACUGAAGUCUACUACAAUUUUAUGAAGCCUACACAGGAAAUGAAUAUCAGCUUAGUCUGGUGCCUACUUGUUUUGUCUUUUGCAAUCAAAGUUCUAUUUUCAUUAACUACACACUAUUUUAAAGUAGAAGAUGGUGGUGAAAGAUCUGUUUGUGUCACCUUUGGAUUUUUUUUCUUUGUCAAAGCAAUGGCAGUGUUGAUUGUAACAGAAAAUUAUCUGGAAUUUGGACUUGAAACAGGGUUUACAAAUUUUUCAGACAGUGCGAUGCAGUUUCUUGAAAAGCAAGGUUUAGAAUCUCAGAGUCCUGUUUCAAAACUUACUUUCAAAUUUUUCCUGGCUAUUUUCUGUUCAUUCAUUGGGGCUUUUUUGACAUUUCCUGGAUUACGACUGGCUCAAAUGCAUCUGGAUGCCCUGAAUUUGGCAACAGAAAAAAUUACACAAACUUUACUUCAUAUCAACUUCUUGGCACCUUUAUUUAUGGUUCUGCUCUGGGUAAAACCAAUCACCAAAGACUACAUUAUGAACCCACCACUGGGCAAAGAAAGUAUCCCUUUAAUGACAGAAGCCACAUUCGAUACUCUGCGACUCUGGUUAAUAAUCCUGCUGUGUGCUUUGCGGUUGGCCAUGAUGCGUAGUCACCUGCAAGCUUAUUUAAAUUUAGCCCAAAAAUGUGUGGAUCAGAUGAAGAAAGAAGCGGGGCGAAUAAGCACGGUUGAGCUACAGAAAAUGGUGGCUCGAGUCUUUUAUUAUCUUUGUGUCAUUGCACUGCAGUAUGUGGCGCCUCUGGUAAUGCUGCUUCACACAACUCUGCUUUUGAAAACACUAGGUAAUCAUUCCUGGGGUAUUUAUCCAGAAUCUAUCUCUACCUUACCAGUGGAUAAUAGUCUACUGUCCAAUUCUGUUUACUCUGAAUUACCAUCAGCUGAAGGGAAAAUGAAGGUAACUGUUACACAAAUAACAGUGGCACUGAGCAGCUUAAAAAAUAUUUUUACUCCUCUUCUUUUUCGAGGACUUCUGUCUUUUCUGACCUGGUGGAUUGCUGCUUGCCUCUUUUCUACAAGCCUUUUUGGGCUUUUCUAUCACCAGUAUCUGACUGUGGCAUGAAUCUCAGUUAACAAAAAAGCAUAUCCAAAUCACCCUUUAAAUUAAAAUAUCUGUGCCCUUAAAGGGCUGAUGAAAACCAGAAGAAAGCAAAUACAAUGGGAAAAAAAAAACAUAUCAGAAUGUCUUGUAUUAAAUGUUUCCUCUGUAUUCUCAGGGUGAAUUAAUGUAGUAAUAUUUAAAAUUACAAAAUAGAUUGUUAACUGUUACACUGUGGCAUUGGAAUUUUAACUCUUUGUAUUUACUGGUAUGAGAGGGCUAUCUACAAGGGUAAUAUUUCUGAUUACCCUGGUUUACAGAAACCUCCAGCAGUCUUUGAAACAUCUCACAUGACUCUAGUUAUUGAUUGCUUUUAAUGGUUUUAUGGUACUGUUGAUAGUCAUAGUGGCUGCCUAUAGAACAAUCUUCAAACUGAGCCAUGCUUUAGGGGAGGGAAAGGGGCUAAAGUCUCUUCUGUUGGUAAUUUAUUAGUUACUCUUGAAACAAUAAAAUCCAACAGAAAGGAAGAGAUAGCUACUGUAUAUUACAGUAAAGAAAGCUGCAUAGUUAUUUUAAAUUUAAUGGAGAUGAAUAUGGUUAAAAUAUAUAACUACUGCUGCUUGAGAAUAGCAAGAGUAUUGUUUUAAAACAUAUUCCACCCAACUUGAGAGUUCUUUUAAAAUGAUUGGCCAUAUGAACAUUUGUAAUCUUGCCAUUAGGUUUGGACCUGCCAUAUUUUGUUUUAUUCUGUGAUCCUAACUAGUUCCUUUUAAUAGGCUAAAAUAUUUAUCAAUACUGAUCAGACUUUAAAGAAAUUACUUUGUAAACCUGCUGACUACCUGUAUGUAUUGUAUAUAUAUUAUAUAUUAAAUAUAUAAUAUAUUGAGAUUAUAAAAGAUGAAAAUAUUGAAUCCUUAUAAUAUUUUAAGUUGCAGAAUGUAUGUUAAAAAGUGACUUGAAUGAGAUGUAUUUGUAUCUAGAAAUUUUAUUUCUUUUUGGAAUGAGAUUAAAAUACAUUUUGAAAGUUCAGCAGAGUAAGCAAUUUAUUUGUGUUGCCUAUGUGUGAGUGUAUUUAAAGUUUUAUGGACGCUUAAUGGUUUCUCCCAAAUUAAAAUUCUUUUUCUGUCAUUUCCAAAAAUCAGAAUCUUUCCCUCUCAAAUCAGGUCUACAGGUAUCAUGUAUGCCUUU